AACAAUAGGAAACGUCAAAAUUGGGAUAGUCGGCAGUUCUGGCCCCUGCAGCUGGAGGUACCCUGAGUUCUGAGGGUCGUAGUGCUGUUUCUGGUAUUCUCAUCGCGGUCACCUCUACCGGUGUGGACAAGUAAAGUUUGAAUCAGCUUCUCCAUGGCCUGGGCACCAGUUCCCGGCUGAGCCAUUUUCCUUUUGGCUAAAAGUCCCCGCCCAGAGGCCAAUUCGUCGCGGCGGCGGUGGAGAUCGCAGGUCGCUCAGGCUUGCAGAUGGGUCAAGGGUUGUGGAGAGUGGUCAGAAACCAGCAGCUGCAACAAGAAGGCUACAGUGAGCAAGGCUACCUCACCAGAGAGCAGAGCAGGAGAAUGGCUGCGAGCAACAUUUCUAACACCAAUCAUCGUAAACAAGUCCAAGGAGGCAUUGACAUAUAUCAUCUUUUGAAGGCAAGGAAAUCGAAAGAACAGGAAGGAUUCAUUAAUUUGGAAAUGUUGCCUCCUGAGCUAAGCUUUACCAUCUUGUCCUACCUGAAUGCAACUGACCUUUGCUUGGCUUCAUGUGUUUGGCAGGACCUUGCGAAUGAUGAACUUCUCUGGCAAGGGUUGUGCAAAUCCACUUGGGGUCACUGUUCCAUAUACAAUAAGAACCCACCUUUAGGAUUUUCUUUUAGAAAAUUGUAUAUGCAGCUGGAUGAAGGCAGCCUCACCUUUAAUGCCAACCCAGAUGAGGGAGUGAACUACUUUAUGUCCAAGGGUAUCCUGGAUGAUUCGCCAAAGGAAAUAGCAAAGUUUAUCUUCUGUACAAGAACACUAAAUUGGAAAAAACUGAGAAUCUAUCUUGAUGAAAGGAGAGAUGUCUUGGAUGACCUUGUAACAUUGCAUAAUUUUAGAAAUCAGUUCUUGCCAAAUGCACUGAGAGAAUUUUUUCGUCAUAUCCAUGCCCCUGAAGAGCGUGGAGAGUAUCUUGAAACUCUUAUAACAAAGUUCUCACAUAGAUUCUGUGCUUGCAACCCUGAUUUAAUGCGAGAACUUGGCCUUAGUCCUGAUGCUGUCUAUGUACUGUGCUACUCUUUGAUUCUACUUUCCAUUGACCUCACUAGCCCUCAUGUGAAGAAUAAAAUGUCAAAAAGGGAAUUUAUUCGAAAUACCCGUCGCGCUGCUCAAAAUAUUAGUGAAGAUUUUGUAGGGCAUCUUUAUGACAAUAUCUACCUUAUUGGCCAUGUGGCUGCAUAAAAAGCACAAUUGCUAGGACUUCAGUUUUUACUUCAGACUAAAGCUACCCAAGGACUUAGCAGAUAUGGGGGUUACAUCAGUGCUGGUCAUUGUAGCCUGAGUAUACAAUCAAGCUUCAGUGUGCAACCUUUUUUUCUUUUGCCAUUUUCUAUUUUAGUAAUUUCCUUGGGGAACUAAAUAAUUUUGCAGAAUUUUUCCUAAUUUUGUUUAUCACGUUUUGCACAAAGCAGAGCCACUGUCUAACACAGCUGUUAACGAAUGAUAAACUGACAUUAUACUCUAAAAGAUGGUGUAUUUGUGCAUUAGAUUUGCCUGAAAAACUUUAUCCAUUUCCAUUCUUUAUACAAAUACCAUGUAAUGUGUACAUAUUUAACUAAAGAGAUUUAUAGUCAUAAUUAUUUUAUUGUAAAGAUUUUAACUAAAGUUUUUCCUUUUCUCUCAAACUGAGUUCUGAAAUUUAUUUGAUUCUGAUCUGAAACUAUUGUCUUCGUAAAAGUUAGAUCUGACUUCAGACAGAAACCAAUACCAGCUUCCUUUUCCUUUAAACUUUGAAGAGUGUUGAUUUGUUACUAUAUUACUAUGCAAAACUGGCAGUUAUUUUUAUAAUAUAAAUUUAUAAUUUGAUUUUUUAUUUUAAAAACUGGGUUAAUCAAGUCUCGGUAAGUCCUUUAAACCAUUUAGGAUUUUUAAAACAUCAAAAUUUAUGAUUUACAUUCAUAGGAAUAAAAUAAAAUAUUAUUAGAACUCUGGUAAA